AAAAAAAGAAUAUGUGUCAGAAGAGAGAAAGGGAGGUAUGGCCUUAAUGCUAUUUUAAUUUAUAAGAUAGAGGCCUGGUAUUCUUGGAUUCUGGAGCCUAUCAAGACAUUUCAAGGUAUAGGUUUGAAUUGAAAAAGUAUGGAAAGAUAAGAUGAGCUUUCAAGAGGGAUGCUGAUCAUAAGUCUUUAGGGUUUAUUGUCUCUGUGACUAUGGUCAGACCAGCUUCACUGUGGAACUGGAACUUAAGAAUGAAAAAGGCAGCAUGCUUUCCAACUGCCUGACUGCUUGUUGGCCUCACCGGUGGGAGCUCCAGCAUCUCCUUUGCUCGAAAUGGACCCCAACUGCUCCUGUGCCACUGGUGGCUCCUGCAUGUGCGCCGGCUCCUGCAAGUGCAAAGAGUGCAAAUGCACCUCCUGCAAGAAGAGCUGCUGCUCCUGCUGCCCCGUGGGCUGUGCCAAGUGUGCCCAGGGCUGCAUCUGCAAAGGGGCGUUGGAGAAGUGCAACUGCUAUGCCUGACGUGGGGACAGCUCUGCUCCCAGAUGUAAAUAGAGUAACCUGCACAAACCUGGAUUUUUUAAAAAAUACAACACUGAGCCAUUUGC